CUUUCUCCUCCUCCAACCUUGGCGGAGGCCACGACUCAGGCGCCACAGCUGGGGGCUAGAGGCCGCGGACCAUGGUGCGGGGCAGCCACCGCUGAAGUCAGCAAAACCGAGCCUGGCCUGAGGCAGGCUGCGCGGGAGGCCAAAGCCAUGGCCAUUGCCACGUCGACCCAGCUGGCCCGGGCACUGUAUGACAACACCGCUGAGUCCCCCCAGGAGCUGUCCUUCCGCCGAGGGGAUGUCCUACGGGUCCUGCAGAGAGAGGGCGCUGGUGGACUGGACGGCUGGUGCCUCUGCUCCCUACACGGCCAGCAGGGCAUUGUGCCCGCCAACAGGGUGAAGCUCUUGCCUGCUGGCCCAGCACCCAAGCCCAGCCUCUCUCCUGCGUCCCCAGCCCAGCCUGGCUCACCAUAUCCAGCCCCAGAUCACAGCAAUGAGGACCAGGAGGUGUAUGUGGUGCCGCCCCCAGCUCGGCCCUGUCCAACCUCAGGACCUCCAGCUGGACCUUGCCCACCCUCUCCUGACCUCAUCUACAAAAUCCCCAGAGCUAGUGGGACCCAGCUGGCUGCUCCCAGAGAUGCCUUGGAGGUCUACGAUGUGCCCCCCACCGCCCUCCGGGUGCCCUCCAGUGGCCCCUAUGACUGCCCUGCCUCCUUUUCCCACCCUCUGACCCGGGUUGCCCCGCAGCCCCCUGGAGAGGAUGAUGCUCCCUAUGAUGUGCCUCUGACCCCAAAGCCACCUGCAGAGCUGGAACCAGAUCUGGAGUGGGAAGGAGGCCGGGAGCCGGGGCCCCCCAUCUAUGCUGCCCCCUCCAACCUGAAACGAGCGUCAGCCUUACUCAAUUUGUAUGAAGCACCCGAGGAACUGCUGGCAGACGGGGAGGGCGGGGGCACUGAUGAGGGGAUCUACGAUGUGCCUCUGCUGGGGCCAGAGGCUCCCCCUUCUCCAGAGCCCCCUGGAGCCUUGGCCUCCCAUGACCAGGACACCCUGGCCCAGCUUCUGGCCAGAAGCCCCCCACCCCCACACAGGCCCCGGCUCCCCUCAGCUGAGAGCCUGUCCCGCCGCCCUCUGCCUGCCCUGCCUGUCCCUGAGGCCCCCAGCCCCUCCCCAGUGCCCUCUCCUGCCCCAGGCCGGAAGGGCAGCAUCCAGGACCGGCCUCUGCCCCCACCCCCACCCCGCCUGCCUGGUUAUGGAGGCCCCAAGGUCGAGGGGGAUCCAGAGGGCAGGGAGAUGGAGGAUGACCCAGCAGGACACCACAAUGAGUACGAGGGCAUUCCGAUGGCCGAGGAGUAUGACUAUGUCCACCUGAAGGGCAUGGACAAAGCUCAGGGAUCUAGGCCCCCGGAUCAGGCCUGCACAGGGGAUCCUGAACUGCCCGAGAGGGGGAUGCCGGCGCCGCAGGAGGCCCUGUCCCCAGGGGAGCCACUGGUUGUGUCCACCGGAGAUCUGCAGCUCCUGUACUUCUAUGCUGGGCAAUGCCAGAGCCACUACUCAGCCCUGCAGGCAGCCGUGGCAGCCCUGAUGUCCAGUACCCAGGCUAAUCAGCCCCCGCGCCUUUUCGUGCCCCACAGCAAGAGGGUGGUGGUGGCUGCUCAUCGCCUGGUGUUUGUUGGGGACACCCUGGGCCGGCUGGCAGCCUCUGCCCCUCUGAGAGCACAGGUCAGGGCUGCAGGUACAGCACUGGGCCAGGCAUUGCGGGCCACUGUGCUGGCUGUCAAGGGAGCUGCCCUGGGCUACCCAUCCAGCCCUGCCAUCCAAGAGAUGGUGCAGUGUGUAACAGAACUGGCAGGGCAGGCCCUGCAAUUCACUACCCUGCUCACUAGCCUGGCUCCAUGAAGGUCCUUUGGCACAGCUCUGCUCCUCCCCUGCCUGCCAAAGCCCCCCUUUAGGCCUUGGGUGGCUGGAAGGCUUUGUUAAGGGACUAGGAGAAAUGGGGGUAUCUUUCCCCUUUCCUGCCCUUUCUGCUCAUCUCAACCUCUCACAGAGGUGUCUUCUCCCCCUAACCUACAGCUUUUUGUACAAGCCAUUUUGUGUAAAUUAUUUAUAUUUAAUAUUAUUCCCUGCUUUGUCAGGAGCAGGUACUAGGCUCUGGGGCAGUGAGGAACUAGAUCCUUCUCUCCUCAGCCUAGGGUGGAGGUCACUGCACUACCACCCACCUCUGGAAGACUGGCUGUGAAAAGUCAGGUGGCAGAAACCUGGGGCCACAUAGAGCCUCUCUCUUUUCCUGUUUCUUGGCUCUAGAAGAUCAGCACUGCACUGUUAGCUGAGAGUGCGGGCAAGACAUAAACUGUCCAGAGUUUGAAGGUUCUCGGAAAGACCGGAGGGCUUCUCCCCACAGAAGGCGGAGAGAGCUGGGGCUCAGACAUGGGUGUGCACCUUAAUAAACCCUGCUGUCUGCCUCCCUGACUCUGCUUCUUGGGAGCAUGGUGAGCAGCCCUGGUGCUCAGCAGCCAUACCUAUGGGACACACACUACGAAAAGGAUGCCUUUAGGGUUUGGGGGAGAUUUUACUCCUUUCUUCAACAACUAUUCACUGGACAAGUUCUCUGCUCCCAUGACGCGCCAGGCACAGUUCUGCAAGUAUAUUGUGAAUGUAUUGUUCUAGUGGGAUACACAAAUAAGUCAGUUAAAAUACAUAAAUAAAAACAUAAACCUGC